GGAAAAGCGCGCGAGCAAGAUGGCCACCACCAAGCGCGUCUUGUACGUGGGUGGACUGGCAGAGGAAGUGGACGACAAAGUUCUUCAUGCUGCGUUCAUUCCUUUUGGAGACAUCACAGAUAUUCAGAUUCCUCUGGAUUAUGAAACAGAAAAGCACCGAGGAUUUGCUUUUGUUGAAUUUGAGUUGGCAGAGGAUGCUGCAGCAGCUAUCGACAACAUGAAUGAAUCUGAGCUUUUUGGACGUACAAUUCGUGUCAAUUUGGCCAAACCAAUGAGAAUUAAGGAAGGCUCUUCCAGGCCAGUUUGGUCAGAUGAUGACUGGUUGAAGAAGUUUUCUGGGAAGACGCUUGAAGAGAAUAAAGAGGAAGAAGGGUCAGAGCCUCCCAAAGCAGAGACCCAGGAGGGAGAGCCCAUUGCUAAAAAGGCCCGCUCAAAUCCUCAGGUGUACAUGGACAUCAAGAUUGGGAACAAGCCGGCUGGCCGCAUCCAGAUGCUCCUGCGUUCUGAUGUCGUGCCCAUGACAGCAGAGAAUUUCCGCUGCCUGUGCACUCAUGAAAAGGGCUUUGGCUUUAAGGGAAGCAGCUUCCACCGCAUCAUCCCCCAGUUCAUGUGCCAGGGCGGUGAUUUCACAAACCACAAUGGCACUGGGGGCAAGUCCAUCUAUGGGAAGAAGUUCGAUGAUGAAAACUUUAUCCUCAAGCAUACGGGACCAGGUCUACUAUCCAUGGCCAACUCUGGCCCAAACACCAAUGGCUCUCAGUUCUUCCUGACAUGUGACAAGACAGACUGGCUGGAUGGCAAGCAUGUGGUGUUUGGAGAGGUCACCGAAGGCCUAGAUGUCUUGCGGCAAAUUGAGGCCCAGGGCAGCAAGGACGGGAAGCCAAAGCAGAAGGUGAUCAUCGCCGACUGUGGGGAGUACGUGUGAGGCGGCACUCUCUCUGCUUCCCCCUCCGCUCUUGACCCUGCAUAUCCAGGAAGGAACUGCCAGCCUCAGAGGAGGCAGCACCGAGGGUGCCUGUUUGAAGCAAGCAGCAUUUGGGAUAUGUGCCCUUCCUCAGGGUCUGCUUGGAGCAGCUCCUCUGCAGGCACAGCCUGGACUAUUCCCAGGCACAGCUGUGGGCCCAGGAGCCAGCUCAGGUGCUCCCCUCCACCAUGGGCAGGCUGUGCAAAAAGCCACUGGCUUUUCUCAGCAUUUGCUGCUGGGCCUCUCCUGGGACUACCAGUGUGGCUCUUACGUGUUUUCUUUGCUAAAAUAAACCCUAGUUCUUAUAUUGCUCUUCCUGCUAGUUCUUGGGAGUUGUCAGAGAUUGUGUCUGUGGCUAAGCUGGACCUCUGAGGCAGGCUGGUGAGUGGGGAGAGCAGAGCAUCUUUUUCACAGCUUUCAUUUCCUCCCUUGGGCCGAUCCCCUUAGAUGUCAGGUGAUGUAUCUUCACACCAGGCAUCGAUGUCAGGGCAACGGAAAUUAAAGACUGGAAAGCUCCGGUCUUCUGCUGCCUCUGCUCCUAAACCCAGCUGCCGGCCUUACAGCCAGCAAGUGUACUCUCAGUGGUUCAUUUGUUUAUUUGUUCACUUUCACCCUACAGAUUUUAAAAAAUGAAAUUUUUAUAACUCAAAGUGCCUUCUCUGUGCCAAGUACUAUGCCUAUUUGUCAGGAGACAGGAAGCCAACAAACUACAUGUGCCUAAUCCAGCCCACUGCCUGUUUUUAUGAAUCAGGUUUUAUUGGAACACAGCCACGUCCAUUUAUUUACAUAUUGUCCAUGGUGGUUUCUUACUGCAGUGGCAGAGGUGCGUAAGGGGCUAUAGACACAAUACAGGCUAUGGUCCCUGUAUUAGGGUUUUCUAGAGAAGCAGAACCAAUAGGGUGUGUAUAUAUGUAGAAAGAGAUUUAUUUUAAGGAACUGGCUCAAGCAGUGGUAGGAGCUGGCAAGUCUGCAAUCUGCACAACAGACCAGCAGGCUGGAGACUCAGGAAAAAAACUGAUGUUGCAGUUCAGCUCUGAGGCAGUUUGGAAGCAGAAUUCUUCCUCCAGUGAUCUCAGUCUUUUUUCUCUUAAGAAUUUCAACUGAUUGGAUGAGGCCUACCCACAUUAUGGAGGGUAAUCUGCUUUACUCUCUACUGACUUAAAUAUUAAUCCAUCUAAAAAAUAGGCCAGGCAUGGUGGCUCAUGCCUAUAAUUCCACCACUAUUGGGAGGCUGAGGCAGGAGGAUCACUUGAGCCCAGGAGUUCAAGACCAGCCUGGGCAAUGUAGAGACCCCCAUCUCUAGGGGGAGAAAAAAAAGCCAGGUAUGGUAGUGCACACCUAUAGUCCCAGCUACUCAGAAGGCUGAGGUGGGAGGAUCGCUUGAACCUGGGAGGUUGAGGCUGCAGUCAGCCAUGGUCAUGCCACUGUACUCCAGCCUGGGUGACAAGAGGGAGACCCUGUCUUGAAAAAAAGAAACCAUCAUCACAGCAACAUCUAGACUAGUGUUUGACUAAAAACUGGAUACCAUGGCCUAGCCAAAUUGACACACAAAAUAGACCAUCACAGUCCCAAGGCCUAAAAUACUUACUAUCUGAGCCUUUACAAAACAGGAUUGCCAGCCACUGAAGAGAACAAAUGGUCCCACCCCCUGCUGAGCUCACAGUCUGGCUCUCCUGUGUGCAGCCACUUCUUGGAGCUGGCUUCUCUCCACUCCCCCUCCAGAUGCUGGUCAGCCAGGCGGUUAUAAAGAAUCUCAUCUGCUGAAGGCUUUUAGCAGGGACUGAGUCCUGUAGCUGUUGGACACCUCCUGUGGGUUGGGUCACUCAGACCAUUCAGAAUCCACUGAGCUGAGCUUUUGCAUCUUGGAUUGAGAUCUGGAUGAGCCAGGAGGCAGGAGAGGCUAGGUGGUCCUCAUGACCCUAGGAUAGCUCUUGCUGAGGGAUGGUGGCAUUCUGCCCUACCUCUGGCUCCCAUGUGCCGACUGGACUUUGUGAGCUCCAGCUGCUACAGUUGACUGAGUUCAGGCUCCAUGUAGCUGGGAUAUACUACAUGGUUACCCCUCACCCCUAUGGAGCUUCCAAAAGAGACCCUCCCUCAAAGCACAGCCCCUUCUCUGAGUGCAAAUAAUGGCCAUCAGAGGUCAGUCACAGGUGUUAGGCAGGCAUCUAUGAAGCUGGGGAUGAUAGCACUGACUUCAGUGCUUGGACGAGAACCAGGAGAGAGUGUGUAGAAAAAGCACAGCCAGCCUCCCAUAAAAGGACAGACUCCUGUGACAACCUUGUCACUCUGUUCCUCCCUGAUACUCUGGGGAGGUGGAGGCCAGUGGGCAGUUCUGAAAGCUCAGCAGGUUUGGAGCCAUUGGGUGUGGACUCCUCUCCCAGUGUUCCUCCUGGGUGUUCACAGAUGUUAUUGAAUGCACACUGGAACCCUGCACAGGUAAACUGAGGCUUUAUUGGCGUGACUGCCAAAGGUCACACAGGGUGGUUUGGCAGAGCUGGGAUUAGAAGCCCAGCCUGUCUCUCUUCAGUAGUAAUGGAGUCCUGGGAGGUUUACUAGGCUUUAGCCUCAAUCUGUGGCGGCAGGGUCCACAGCCCUGGGGAGUGACACAGUCAUGGUCCCCAUGAUUGGCCAGGACCUGUGUGGAGAGACACAGGAGACAAGACCCUGCUCUUCCAGGCCAGAAGGGAGGGGAGCCCCAGAGCUGGGCAGUGGCAUGCCCCACAGCCUGGCCACCUGCUUCGGCUACGCACCAUGCAGCAGCUGCACCUGGCUGCCUCGGGAAAACUCUGACCUCUCUGGGAAGUGGAGCCAGUGGCUCUGUGGGCGUCCUUUCCUGCAGCCUGGAGAGCAAAGCGGCUUUCCCUGGGACUGUGUGGCUCCUGUCCCAACUGGCCUCCCCAUUCCACAUUCCCAUUGCUGGACCAGCACCAGGACUGGGCACAGGGCUUCCUUUUGCUGAUUCAUUUCCCCCCUAACUCAUUCAGAGUUGAGCCCCAUCUGAGUCCCCACAUGCUGGCCCUGAAACGGUUACAAAGGCUGAAACCAGGGAUGGCAGGCCCAGGAUCAGUGCUGUGGCUGUUGGAGUGUCCUCUCCAACAGCAUGACAGCCGCCUCCAGGUGCUCCCAGCAUCUGUUGCAGUCAUGGCAGCCUCACGGCAACCUCUGAAGAAGGAAUUAUAGAACCAACUUUUUAUUGUUGAAAAUGGAGUCUUGUAGAGUUCAGUGAUGGGAAACUAAAGUAGAAAAAGCACAUCACAAAGAAACAUAUAUAGUACAGUGUGAUCCCAAUUUUGUAAAAAUAUCUGUAAUAUGUAAGCAUAGGUAUUUGUAUAUCUUAAGAAAAAAAGCCUAGAAAUAAAGCCACAAAAAUAUUAA